UCCGCGCUCGUUGCCCCCGGCCCAUCGCCCAGCCCGCGUCGAAGGCAUUGACCGGGCGGCCCAAAUGCCAGGCCCGGCGGGCGGGGCCCCGACGUCAGCGGCUGACGAUCCGGCCCAUCUGCGGCCUCAGCCAGGCCGGGCCCCAGAGUCACGCUCGGCGACGAGGAGGCCGCGCCUUAGGAGUAUUGUCCCAUUUGAGGCCUCGCGGCCCCCCCUACAGCAGGCUGGGCGGGCAGGGGCCGCCAGCCCCACGGGACAGUAGCGGAGGCUGAGAUGGGAAGGGACAGGCCCAGGGUCACGCAUCUAUUAGAGGCGGGAGCCUCACGCCGGGGCAGGGAUUUUGGAAUUAGACACUUUAAAACGCCUCAUAUUCUACUUUUGCCAAAGAGAAAGAUUGUGUCGUUUACAAGAGAGAUAGUAGAUUUUUUUAAAAAAGAUUACUGUAGCAGAUUUUAUUUAAUUUUUUUUUUUGAGAGGGAGUCUCGCUCUGUUGCGCAUGCUGGAUGGAGUGCAGUGGCACGAUCUCGGCUCACUGCAAGCUCCGCCUCCCGGCUUCAAGGGAUUCUCCUGCCUCAGCCUCCCAAGUAGCUGGGACUACAGGCGCCUGCUACCACGCCUGGCUAAUUUUUCUAUUUUUGGUAGAGACUGGGUUUCACUAUGUUGGCCAGGCUGGUCUCGAACCCCUGACCUCGUGAUCUGCCCGCCCCGGCCUCCCAAAGUGCUGGGAUUACAGACGAGAGCUACCGCGCCCGGCCAUUUUAAAAUUUUUUAAUUAAAAAAGUAUAUAUAUAUACGUGUGUGUGUGUGUGUGUGUGUGUGUGUGUGUGUGUGUGUAUAUAUAUAUAUAUAUAUAUUUUUUUUUUAGACACAGUCUCACUCUCACCCAGGGUGGAGUGUAGUGGCGGGAUCUCAUCUCACUGCAACCUCUGCCUCUGCCUCCCGGGUUCAAGGUAUUCUCCUGCCUCAGCCUCCCAAUCCCAAGUAGCUGGGAUUACAGGCGCAGGUGCCUGUCUCAUUUAUAUCUAUCUAUCUAUCUGUCCAGAUACAUAUCUAUAUGAAUAAGUUUAUUCAUAAGAAUACACUAUAAGUAUUCCUAUACAGAAUUUUUCUCCUGGAGAAGGAAGAAUCACAUCAGUUUUUUUGGCAUCUUCAUCUAUAUAAGUUAGGCCAGUUUAGCAGAUUUUAGAAUCUUGGUUUGAUAUAGUGCAGUAUGUCCAAUUGGGAGAUUAUAAUCCUUUGGCCAUUUUUGACAUACUGGAAAACGCUUGUAAAGGCUCAAUAGAUGAUACCUACUAUUAUUAAUACACCUCAGUGAAGGUUUUGAAACCUUGAUUUUUCUGGAUACUUUUAUUAAAGUAUAACUUCCUCUCCCUCCUCUUAGUGAGUGUGCUGAGCUUCUUUUUGGGUUCCCUGAGUGCAAGGGAGAGAAAAAGCGUUGAGGAUUCUGCAGGUUUAUAGUCCUGUUCCCUGGGAAGAGGGGGCCCUAGAAGGUGACAUCAUCCACUCCCCCUAGCCUGGGGCUCACUGCUUCACUACCUUUCAGAUCACUCCUGUCCACCUGCUCCUCCCUUCUUGCAGCACUUGAGAUCCCAAAAAACUCCCCAAAAGGGACAGAUUUGCCCUGGACUCUUGUUAGCCCAUCCUAUCACACUGUUGUUGUUUAUAAGUAUUCCUAUACAGAAUUUUUCUCCUGGAGAAGGAAGAACCACAUCAGUUUUUUCUUCAUCUUCACUGUACAUUUACUAUGAUAGGUGUUCAGUAAUUGUUAUUGAAUGAAUGAAGCAAUUAUAGAUUACUAGUGCUAAGGGGGAGGGGCAGUGAAAAUCUCUAGGAUGCGUUGUCUAUGCUAGAAUCUUAAAAACGAGAGAGACUCAGGCAUACAGAGGAUGCAUAUUGAGAGCUGAUGUGAAGUUGGAGGAGGGCCGGGUGGGUCCUCGGAAUCCACAGGAGGCUGGCAUGGCUGGAGCACGACAGGAACUGGAUGGCUCAAGGUCAAGAGAGGUCGGCUGGGCCAUGAAGAAGUCUAGAUCUUAUGCCAGGACCCCGAGACAGACAAGCACACAGAGGACCAGAGUCCUUCGACACCCUUGCCCCAGCCAGCUGCUGAGAAGAACUCGUACCUCUACUCCACGGAAAUCACACUGUGGACGGUGGUGGCCGCCAUUCAGGCCUUGGAGAAGAAGGUGGAUUCCUGCCUGACCCGCUUGCUGACUCUGGAGGGGCGCACGGGGACAGCCGAGAAGAAGCUGGCCGACUGCGAGAAGACAGCUGUGGAGUUCGGGAACCAGCUGGAGGGCAAGUGGGCCGUGCUGGGGACCUUGCUGCAGGAGUACGGGCUGCUGCAGAGGCGGCUGGAGAAUGUGGAGAACUUGCUGCGCAACAGGAACUUCUGGAUCUUGCGGCUGCCCCCGGGCAGCAAGGGGGAGGCCCCCAAGGUGCCCGUGACCUUCGAUGAUGUGGCCGUGUAUUUCUCUGAGCUGGAGUGGGGCAAGCUGGAGGACUGGCAGAAGGAGCUCUACAAGCACGUGAUGAGGGGCAACUACGAGACGCUGGUCUCCCUGGAUUAUGCAAUCUCCAAACCAGACAUCCUCACCCGGAUAGAGAGGGGAGAGGAGCCUUGUCUUGACCGGUGGGGCCAGGAGAAGGGGAAUGAAGUAGAGGUGGGACGUCCAAGGAUGAUGGGCACUGGCCUCCCUCCGUAUCCAGAGCACCUCACCAGCCCACUUAGCCCUGCCCAGGAGGAGCUGAAAGAAGGGCAGGCCCCCAAGCAGCAGCAGGACUCAGAGGCGAGAGUGGCCCCAGCCGGGCCAGAAGCAGGUGGUGGUGUGGCCAUCAAGACAGAGGCACAGUCUGAAGACGAGAUGACGCCUGAGCGGCUCUUUCUGGGGGUGUCCCGAGGCCAGACCGAGUGUAGAAUCCCCCGAGGGCCCAGGAACAGGCCUGGGGGCCCCAGCCGUCAUCAGGCCCAGGGCAUGCCCAGGGUGCGGGCAGGGGAGCCACGGCCACCGGGGGCCAGUGGGGAGACGCCCCGAGUCCUCUCCCGCAGGCGGCAGCGGGCAUUCCCCUGCCCCGACUGCGGGCAGAGCUUCCGCCUGAAGAUCAAUCUGACGAUUCAUCAGCGGACCCAUGUGGAGGAGGGGCGGCAGGAGGCCCCCGGCCGCUCGCCCACCAGCUGCGGGGACAGCCAGGCCAUGCUGGAGCCGGGGGAGGUGGUGGUACCCGGCCCUGUCAUCCGCUGGCUCCCCGAGGAGCCUGAGGGUCGCCGCUCCGUGGCAGGGGGCCGUGCCUUGGUGGGGCGGCGGCCUGCAGCCAGCAAGAUGUACCACUGCAGCGAGUGCCUGCGCUUCUUCCAGCAGCGCAAGAGCCUGCUGCUGCACCAGCGCCUGCACACCGGCAAUGGCCAGGGCUGGCCCGCCUGCCCCUACUGCGGCAAGGCCUUCCGCCGGCCCUCGGACCUCUUCCGGCACCAGCGCAUCCACACCGGUGAGCGGCCCUACCAGUGCCCCCAGUGUGGCCGGACCUUCAACCGCAACCACCACCUGGCCGUGCACAUGCAGACCCACGCCCGAGGCCAGGUGGGCCCACACUUCCCUGCCGCCCCCGCCCGCCACGGGAGCCUGCCCCUGCCCUGGCCCAGCCGGAAGGAGGAGGGCUGACCUGGCAGGAGCCCACAGAGGACCCCUGGCGGGGUCUCUCCCCUGUGCCUGACGCAGGUUCUUCCUUUUCCUGGGAUGGAGAGAGGUUUGUUGUUUUUACCCAUUCAAAUGGGAAGCUAGCUGCCCUUCUGGUGACAUUGUGUGUGACCGGGUGCUUUCUGUUUCCUGUUUGCACUCUUCGCUGCCUUUUCUGCAUUCCUGACUUCUAAAAGAUGCCUUAAGGCUUAAGGGAUGCCAUAUUUUUGAUAAGGCCUCUGGUAGGUACCACAGCCAAGAGGACCAGAGAUCAUGGCCCUUCCAGUAUGGGGGCGAUAGAGACAUCGGGGACCUGGGAUUUUUGUUUUGUGCAGAGAUCUCCUGCCUGCUGUCACCAUGAGAAACAGUGGAGUGGAGUGGAUGGAUGGCCUGACUUGAAGAAAGGGCCCUGGAAAGUUUUCUACUUUGCUAUUUUGAAAUUUUUUUCCCUUCUUAUAGAGACUUUGAAAUACUUUUGUAAAUGUGUGUAGUUGUUAAUGGAACUUUGCCUUUUGCAAAGUCGGAAAGAGUCGGCUUUUCCAUGUGAGGCUCGCAGAGCUGAAAGGGGAGCUACGUCCACCAGCCUGUGGGUCUUUUGGUUUUUUUUUUGUUGUUGUUGUUGUUUUUUUAAGAUGGAGUUUCACUCUUGUUGCCCAGGCUGGAGUGCAAUGGUACAAUCUCCGCUCACUGCAACCUCCGCCUCUCGGGUUCAGGUGAUUCUCCUGCCUCAGCCUCCUGAGUAGCUGGGAUUACAGGCGCCCACCACCACUCCCGGCUAAUUUUUGUAUUUUUAGUAGAGACAGGGUUUCAUCAUGUUGUCCAGACUGGUCUCGAACUCCUGAUGUUAGGUGACCCGCACACCUCGGCCUCCUGAAGUGCUGGGAUUACAGGCGUGAGCCACCACUCUUGGCCCAGCCUGUGGGUUUUGAUGGGGAUGUCUUGGCUGCUGUCUUGGAGGCACAGUGUCUCCCCAUGUGUGUGUUUCUUGGCCCAGAGUGACUCCCAGUAUUCCUAGUCCUUCCCCACAGGAUAGUCACAUCCAUUAUUUACUUUUGUUGUCAGCUGGGAGGGGAAACUGAAGCCUGGACACGUCUCCCCAAGGGCUCAGUGUUCAUGGGUGUGUAAGAUCCAUUGACUGGACCCCAGAAAGCACCCUGAGGGGCAGUGCAGAGAGAGCCCAGGAAGCCCCUCCACUAGAGGAGGCCCUUGGUCUGGCUGAGGACCACGUCCACCCUGGGCCUCCAGGCCUGCUUUUCACAUUAAAGGCGGGGCAGUCUCCUCUCAAAGGAGUUCUCCCUUGAGCACUUUGGGCUCUGGGGCAGAGUUGGGCUAGGAGAUCUGGGUGAAUCCUUUAGUCACAGCUAGUCUCAUGUUCCUCUUCUGUCAAAGGGGUCAUGGCCCCAGUGUGUCCUACCUCAGAGUUGUCAGGGUCAAAGUAACAGGCACUGGGACAAAUAUGAAGCCUAGCUUUGUGCUUCCUUUCAAAUUCAGGGCCUCCUUUCUACUCCAUUCCAGCCUUUUUUUCCUGUCAGAAUCCCUCAGGAAGGACCUUUAUCUUCUGGAGUGAGUGGCAGUUCCACUGGGUUCAGUGAAAGAGUCGCCCAUGGGGCUCUGUUCCCCAGGAGUCCUUUGUAUUUUGGUGAACAAAUUCUUACCAAAGCAUGAGAUUCGGACUGUAGAAGUUCAGACUGCCUCAGUUCAGACUGCCUCAUGGGGCAGUCUGGAGGUCAGCUGGCUUCUGGUGUCUCUCAUCACACCACUGCGGACGCUGUCUGUAGAGCAGCCUUGGUGUGGGUGACUCUGAAGCUGGAGUGAUGGGACCCCAGCUAUCCUUGUUUUUUACCGCCUUGUCUGGCACUGUGACCACGCUUCAGGGCUGCUUCUGGGGGUCUUGGUCCCUGGAUGUGCCAUUUCCUUGCCCUUCUGACCCUCACACUUCUUCCAAAGUCUUGAGCAGAGUUGGGGGCCAAUGGUAGCAUUGCUGUCAUCUCUGGGAGGAGAGUGAGUAUACAAGUCAGUGACAGUUCAGCCAGGCUCCCUUGGGUUUGGGAAGAGGCACUGCCCUUCUGUGCUGUGGAUCCUGCUUGUCUGCUCUGGAGUCCCCCCACCCUUGCCAGGAGCUUCACAAACCAGAGACGGGCUGUCAGCAAGAGCUCAGACAGGAUGUGGUGCAAGUGCAGGUGCACGAGUUUAACCCUCAGCUGCAGGAGCUAGUCUCAGGUGUUCUGGGGAUGCCUCAGGCUAAGAAUUUUGCCGACUUUCUGGGCUUGGUUGGCUAAUGCCAAAUGCCCCUGCUUAAAUAUCACAAGGUGCUGAUUCUCCUUUUUUCUUUUUUUCAUACCAAUGUGCUCAAACUUUGAGCUAGGUCUUGUGAGUUUGCCUAGCACUCAGACCUGUUUAAGUAACGUUCUUUACAUUGAAACAAGUCAACCGAAGCUUUGUGGUGCAGGAGCUGAGGGUGCCCCAGACUCAGUGGGAGCCCUGGUUGGGCCCCAAACUCUCCCAGCAGGGUCCUCGGUUUCCUCAUUUGUGAAAUAAAUGAGUGGGCCACGACGUUAAUAAGCCCAAGAGAACUGUGAAGGUGGUAGUCCCUUGCCCUAAUUGGUGCUCAAUAAAGUUGUUGGCAUAAACGAGUG